AUGAACCUCUGUCUUUCUGCAUUACUCUUUUUCCUGGUGAUCUUACUGCCUUCAGGAAAAGGUAUGUUUGGGAAUGAUGGAGUCAAAGUUCGCACCUGCACUAGCCAGAAAGCCGUAUGUUUCUUCGGGUGUCCGCCAGGAUACAGGUGGAUUGCGUUCUGCCACAAUAUUCUGUCUUGCUGUAAAAAUAUGACACGUUUUCAACCCCCGCAAGCCAAAGAUCCAUGGGUUCAUUAA